GGGGGGAGGGGAAGGGAGGUCGCGGAGGGGGAGGGGAGAGAGGCAACCCCUGGCUGCGGUGGCCAGGAGGCGCGCCUGGGGGGCUCCGGGAGGGGAGUGCGCCAGCUAAUGCCUUGGUGCAGCCUGCCUCCAAGCGUUUGGAUUGAGAGGAGAGGGGCUUUGGGAGGUUUGGGGCGGCCGGCGCCCAAUACCCGAAGGAGCUCGGAAGGGUGUGGAGUGGCGCCUACGGGAAUAAGUUGAUUGGGGUCAUAGAAUCGGAGCCUAGUUCCUUGGCUAAGUCAGCGCUUAAUCAAGCGCCGGCUGGAGGCCCAGCCUGGUUUAUAGUGAUGAUUCUAGCUAACUUUAAGAGUUUGCUUUGCUGGACACUACAGUAAGUAUUUUGGAUGCACUGUCUCAUUUAAUCAUCACAAGGAUUCCUCCAAAUUCAGAUAUGGUUGUUUUCAUUUCGAAUGUGAUGAAAGUGAGCCUUGGAGGACUUAAGAUCACAUAGCUAGUAGUGAGAAUCUUUACCGUCUUGCUGCACUGCCUUUGAGGCAGGGUUUGAGGCCUCUUGGCAUUCUUUAGAAUAAUUACAGGUUGACUUGGCUUAGUAUUUCUUGAAGGAAACUGCUCCCCUCAGGAGGUGCUUAAGCCACAGCCUCUGAAAUUGAGCAGGGUCUUACCCUUAGAGGUAGUAGAACCAGAAGUUUGUCCGCCGAACCUAGAACCUGGUUCAGGAGGCAGGCUUUUUAUAUGACCUUGGGCGUGUCAGAUUAUUCCCAGUGCUGAGAAAAGUGUACCUGGUAGAGGGUUAUAUUAUACAAGUUAGAAGCCGAGUCAUUUCUGGACUUCAGAGGGGGCGGGGCAAGGACAAGAUGGGAGAAGAGCUUGUCGUAGGGCUCCUACUGGCAGUUCUAGGAACUAGUUAAUACCAGUCUCUACUUUGGAAGAGAAAAUGAGUACCAGAAUUCUGUAUGUGAAGUAAUGUUGGGUUGGGAUUUCCCCUUGAAGGGAAAGUUUUGUUGCACACUUACUUUUGAGAUACUUUUGUGUUUACUCUGGGGAGAUGACUGCAAGAGCAAACGACAGCUUUAGGAAAGAAGCACUGGUUCCUGGCCACAAGAUGUUUACAGUCAAUAGGAAACACAAAAAGUGAAUUUGCAGUCUUUCUCUAGAGUUGUAUAUAUAGAACAUCCUGGAGUCCACCAUGAACGGACAGUUGGAUCUAAGUGGGAAGCUAAUCAUCAAAGCUCAACUUGGGGAGGAUAUUCGGCGAAUUCCUAUUCAUAAUGAAGAUAUUACUUAUGAUGAAUUAGUGCUAAUGAUGCAACGAGUUUUCAGAGGAAAACUUCUGAGUAAUGAUGAAGUAACAAUAAAGUAUAAAGAUGAAGAUGGAGAUCUUAUAACAAUUUUUGAUAGUUCUGACCUUUCCUUUGCAAUUCAGUGCAGUAGGAUACUGAAACUGACAUUAUUUGUUAAUGGCCAGCCAAGACCCCUUGAAUCAAGUCAGGUGAAAUAUCUCCGUCGAGAACUGAUAGAACUUCGAAAUAAAGUGAAUCGUUUAUUGGAUAGCUUGGAACCACCUGGAGAACCAGGACCUUCCACCAAUAUUCCUGAAAAUGAUACUGUGGAUGGUAGGGAAGAAAAGUCUGCUUCUGAUUCUUCUGGAAAACAGUCUACUCAGGUUAUGGCAGCAAGUAUGUCUGCUUUUGAUCCUUUAAAAAACCAAGAUGAAAUCAAUAAAAAUGUUAUGUCAGCGUUUGGCUUAACAGAUGAUCAGGUUUCAGGGCCACCCAGUGCUCCUGCAGAAGAUCGUUCAGGAACACCCGACAGCAUUGCUUCCUCCUCCUCAGCAGCUCACCCACCAGGCGUUCAGCCACAGCAGCCACCAUAUACAGGAGCUCAGACUCAAGCAGGUCAGAUUGAAGGUCAGAUGUACCAACAGUACCAGCAACAGGCCGGCUAUGGUGCACAGCAGCCGCAGGCUCCACCUCAGCAGCCUCAACAGUAUGGUAUUCAGUAUUCAGCAAGCUAUAGUCAGCAGACUGGACCUCAACAACCUCAGCAGUUCCAGGGAUAUGGCCAGCAACCAACUUCCCAGGCACCAGCUCCUGCCUUUUCUGGUCAGCCUCAACAACUGCCUGCUCAGCCGCCACAGCAGUACCAGGCGAGCAAUUAUCCUGCACAAACUUACACUGCCCAAACUUCUCAGCCUACUAAUUAUACUGUGGCUCCUGCCUCUCAACCUGGAAUGGCUCCAAGCCAACCUGGGGCCUAUCAACCAAGACCAGGUUUUACUUCACUUCCUGGAAGUACCAUGACCCCUCCUCCAAGUGGGCCUAAUCCUUAUGCGCGUAACCGUCCUCCCUUUGGUCAGGGCUAUACCCAACCUGGACCUGGUUAUCGAUAAGGAGGCUCCUCUACACCAAUUAAUGUAGCUGCUAGCUAUUGGCCUCCCAAAAGACUCCAGUACUAUUUUAAUUUGUAUUGAAGAAGUUCAGAAAUUUAAAAGCAGAGCAUUUUUUAUGAUAUCAUUGUUGGUGUUAAUUGAAAGUAUAAUUUGCUGGAACACAAAGACCAAAAUGAAAGUUUUUUCCUCCCUGCUUAAAAAUGUAGCAGCUUCUUAGUUACUUUGGAACACUACUCUUACAUGUAUAAAGUGAUUGACUUGACUUUCUAGCUUCCCUUGUCCGGAGGAUAUUAAAAUGCUAGGGUGAGGUUUAGCCAUCUUACUUGGCUUUUUACUAUUAACAUGAUGUACUAAAGUAGAGCCCUUUGAGAAUACAAGAUAUUAUGUAUAAAAUGUAACACUGAUGAUAGGUUAAUAAAGAUGAUUGAAUCCAUUA